AUGCGCGGUUGCCCGGAGGCCUACUGGAGAUUCAGUAUCUCUCGGUUAUUUCCUGCGAUCACUAAAGCCAGUUUUCAAGAAAACAAGUCGCAGGGGUUUGAAAUGUCACACCAAGUGACCUGGGCACGGCAUAUCCAGGGGCCAUUCCCAGCUCCCUCCCACCCGGGCCACCCCCGACCCCCUCCACUUCGGUCUGGAAAGAAAAUAAACCAAGGACACGCCAGACUGGUUCUGGGUGGACUUAUUUUCCCGGCAGCCGCGCUCCUAGCGGGGGCUCGUUGCGGCCCCUCGGUGUAUCGCUUGCAGGUGAUGCCAAACGCAGAUAAGCAGCCGCCGCCCGGCCCCCGCCUCUGUCUAGACUGUGGAAUUAAUAAAUGCCGCGGAUUGAUCACGUCGCGCAUCCACUCCGGGGACAGCGCGGGGCACGGCCCGUCACGGCCGCCCGCUCUGGCCGGGGUUGGCCUCACUGCUGUGCUGCAGGGCCAGGGGCAGCGCGCGGGGCUUCGAGCCUCACCCAGGGCCGCGGACCGCUGGGGAAGGAAGCGCCGGGAGGGCCCGCGGCGCCGAGCGAGAGUGGGGCUCGGGGCUCGGCAGGCGCCAGGCCAAGGCUGGUUCCGGGAGCGGGGCGCGCCCUCGCCCGCAUAACCCUAGGCCGGAGUCCGCCGCUCAACCGCCACAAGUGCCGCAGGUUUCCCGCCCAAACGGGUCCCGCCUCCUGCCCGCGGGCCUGGGCCGCCAGGUGCCCAGGGGUCGCCAAUGGGGCGCUCCUGCUUCUGGGAGGGCCCUCAGCGCGCAUGCGCCCAGCCCCACCCCCUCGGCCGCGCCCAAUCCCCACCGGGCCCGCCCCGCCCGCAGCACGCGGAGCCCCGGCAGCCGACGCCAGCCUGACCCCUGAACUGGCCUCCGCCGGCCCUCCCGCCGCGCCAACAGCACAGAGGAGUGGCGUCGCCCCGGGUUAUUAUUUUUUAUUAAGAUCAAAAUACAAGUCCCACUAUGAACUGGCUGUUCUCACAAUAAAUAACAAUAACUUAC